UGCGCCCGGGCUCCCCUCUCCGCCGGCCCGGCACUUCCCAGCUCUGACGCGGGAGCUUCUUUCACACCAAUGGGGCUCGCGCGCGGAGGGGCCCUGCCCCUCCUCCGGGAAGGUGUGUCCCUGUUUCCUCACCUGAAACUUCCUAGGAGAACCCGAUCCCUCCCUCCCGUCGGGCGGCCAGGGGCGGGCCGCGGGUGGGGCGGCCGGGCCUGCGCUGGGGACGGCUCUGGGGACUGCGGCCGGCGCCGGGACCUGGAGGGGACGCUGGGGCCGAAGCAGCAUGUGACACCGACCAGGAUUCAGCCCUGAUGGAGGCUGAGGAGGCCCAGCAUGGAGCCUCUCCUCCCAUCUCUGCCAUAGAGGAAUUCAGCAUUAUCCCUGAGGCUCCCAUGAGGAGCAGCCAGGUCUCUGCCUUGGGGCUUGAAGCUCAAGAAGAUGAGGACCCAUCCUAUAAGUGGAGAGAGGAACACAGACUCUCAGCAACUCAGCAGAGUGAGUUAAGGGAUGUGUGUGACUAUGCGAUUGAGACGAUGCCCUCUUUUCCCAAGGAAGGUUCUGCAGAUGUGGAGCCCAAUCAGGAAAGCCUUGUGGCUGAGGCCUGUGACACUCCGGAACACUGGGAGGCAGUACCCCAGAGCCUAGCAGGCCGACAAGCAAGGACUCUAGCUCCCCCAGAGCUCUGGGCCUGCCCCAUUCAGAGUGAGCAUCUAGACAUGGCCCCAUUUUCCAGUGACCUGGGAAGCGAAGAAGAGGAGGUGGAAUUUUGGCCAGGACUUACUUCUUUGACAUUGGGAUCUGGACAGGCAGAAGAAGAAGAGGAAACCUCUUCAGAUAACUCUGGUCAGACCAGAUAUUAUUCUCCCUGCGAAGAGCAUCCUGCAGAGACCAACCAGAAUGAAGGCGCUGAAAGUGGGACUAUCAGGCAGGGGGAAGAGCUGCCAUCUGAGGAGCUGCAGGAAAGUCAAGGGCUCUUGCAUCCCCAGGAGGUCCAAGUUCUGGAGGAGCAGGGACAGCAGGAAGCAGGAUUUCGGGGGGAAGGAACUCUGAGGGAGGAUGUUUGUGCCGAUGGGCUAUUAGGGGAGGAACAGAUGAUAGAGCAGGUUAAUGAUGAAAAGGGAGAACAGAAGCAAAAACAGGAACAGGUACAAGAUGUGAUGCUUGGGAGACAAGGAGAAAGAAUGGGGCUCACUGGGGAGCCAGAGGGUCUGAAUGACGGUGAGUGGGAGCAGGAGGAUAUGGAGAGGAAGGCUCAGGGUCAGGGAGGUCCAGAACAGGGAGAAGAGAGGAAGAGGGAGCUGCAGGUGCCAGAAGAGAACAGGGCGGACUCUCAGGACGAAAAGAGUCAAACCUUUUUGGGAAAAUCAGAGGAAGUAACUGGAAAGCAAGAAGAUCAUGGUAUAAAGGAGAAAGGGGUCCCAGUCAGCGGGCAGGAGGCGAAAGAGCCAGAGAGUUGGGAUGGGGGCAGGCUGGGGGCAGUGGGAAGAGCGAGGAGCAGGGAAGAGGAGAAUGAGCAUCAUGGGCCUUCAAUGCCCGCUCUGAUAGCCCCUGAGGACUCUCCUCACUGUGACCUGUUUCCAGGUGCCUCAUAUCUCGUGACUCAGAUUCCCGGGACUCAGACAGAGUCCAGGGCUGAGGAACUGUCCCCCGCAGCUCUGUCUCCCUUGCUAGAGCCCAUCAGAUGCUCUCACCAGCCCAUUUCUCUACUGGGCUCCUUUUUGACUGAGGAGUCACCUGACAAGGAAAAACUUCUAUCAGUACUUUGAUAUGUCACAGUUUCAUGUUUAUCCAGUUCAAUGUAUUUUUAAAUUUUUCCUUGAGACUUCUUUGACUGAUAGAUUAUUGUGAAGUGUGUUUUUAAAUUUCCAAAUGUUUAGGGAUUUUCAUAUCUUUCUUAUGCUGAUUUCCAAUUGGAUUCCCUACAAUGAUUUCUGGUUUUCAUCUGCUCUGGAUGAUUACUAUCUCUUUUAAAUUUGUUGUGGCGAGUUUUAGGGCCUAGGACAGCUCUAUCUUGCCAUGUGUUUCGUCAGCACUCAAAAAAAAUAUGUGUAUUCUGCUGUUACUGUGUGGAAUAUUCUGUAAAUGCCAAAUAGAUUCUUUUGGUUAAUGGCAUUUUGAGUUGUUUUAUAUUCUUGUUGAUUUUCUUUUUUUUCCUCUUUUUAAAAACAUGAAAUGCUUCACAAAAUUUUGUGUAAUCUAUAUUCAAGAACCAUUUUAAUCUUGUUGGCAUCAUUCUGAUUUUAGAAAGUGCUGCCAAAGCCAACACUCCUUGCUGAUUUUCUGUCUAGUUCUAUCAAUUAUUGAAAAAGGCAUGAGGAAAUUUCUAACUAUAAUUGUGGAUUCAUCUAUAUCUCCUUUCAGUUUUCUUUUUUUAAAAAAAAUCAAUGAAAAUUUAUUAAAUUAAGCAUAAAGUUACUUUCACAUUUAUCUACAACCACAGUGAAUACAGUUCUUGGCAUGAAGACACCACAACCUUUAGAAUUUAAAGCCUCCUCACCUGCAAGAUUACAUAUAUAAAACUCCCACUAUUGUUUCUCUAAGAGUGGAUUAGUUCACCAAGUUAAAAGUUAUAUGAUCUAGAAUAUAAUAAAAUGGAAAUGAUUUACUCAUAA